AUUACAGGCAUAAGCCACCGUGCCUGGCACAGUAUAGUGAUAUAAUUGUUCUAUUUUAUUAUUGGUUGUUAGUCUCUGACUGUGCCUAACUUAUAAACUUCAUCUUAGGUAUGUACAUAUAGGAAAAACAUAGUAAGUAUAGGCUUCAGUGCUAUCCAUGGUUUCAGGCAUCCACUGGGGGUCUUGGAACAUAUCCUAUGCAGAUAAAGAGGGAUGACUGUAGACAUAUAUAAAGUAGAACAAGGGGUUAGCAAGAGACAGGGGCUUCCUUAGACCGAGUGGUCAGGAAAGCAUGUCCAGGAAGUGACCCAAGCAGAGGGUGGCAGGAUGUAAGGUCGGUCAGCACCAAAGACCAGGUCCUGCAGGCAUUUUAGCCAUAGUAAGGAGUUUGGAGGGUCAAGACUGGGAGGGUGACAUGAUCUGAUUUACUUUUUUUUUUUUUUUUGAGACAGAGUUUUGCUAUUGUCGCCCAGGCUGGAGUAUAGUGGUGCGAUCUCGGCUCACUGCAACCUCCGUCUCCUGGGUUCAAGUGAUUCUCCUGCCUCAGUCUCCCAAGUAGCUGGGAUUACAGGCACCCACCACCAUGCCCAGCAAAUUUUUUAUGUGUGUACUGUUUUAGUAGAGACAGGGUUUUGCCAUGUUGGCCAGUCUGGUCUCGAACUCCUGACCUCAAGUGAUCCACUCGCCUCGGCCUCCCAAAGUGCUGGGAUUACAGGCGUGAGCCACUGCGCCCAGGCUGACUUCCUUUUGAAAAGAUCUCACUGACUAUCUAGGGACGACUGUAAUGAGGCGGGAUUGGAAAAAGGGAGGCCAGCAGUAUUGAGGAGAGAGGCAGGUGGUAGAGGUUGCAUCUGGGGUGUGGUCCAAAGAUCAAUAUCAUCAUCACCAUCACCACCAUCAUCACCAUCAUCAUGCCCCUGCUUUGGCAUCAAUAGGAUUAGUAAGAUGAGCCCCUUAUUUCUAAGCAUCAAAUGUGAACAAUACAAAGUGCUCUGUGAAAUGCAAAUUCCAGACUUAUCAUGGGCCAGGCACAGUGCCUCACACCUGUAAUCUCAACACUUUGGGAGGCUGUGGUGGGAGGAUUGCUUGAGGCCAGGAGUUUGAGACCAGCCUGGGCAACAAAGUGAGACCCCAUCUCUACAAAAAAAUAUAAAAUUAAGGCCAGGCAUGGUGGUUCACCCCUGUAAUCCCAGUACUUUGGGAGGCUGAGGCAGGCGGAUCAGAUGAAGCCGGGAGUUCGAGACCAGCCUGGGCAACAUGGCAAAACCCCAUCUCUACAAAAAAUACAAAAGUUAGCCCAGGAUGGUGACAGAUAUCUGUAAUCCCAGUCACUCAGGAGGAUGAGGCACAAGAAUGGCAUGAACCCAGGAAGCAGAGGUUGCAGUUAGCUGAGAUCGUGCCACUGCACUCCAGCCUGGGCAACAGAGGAAGACUUUCUCGGACCCCUCCAGACUCACCAGCUGCAGCUGUCUCGACUGCUCUGUGGCACUGUCCUGUAUAGCCCUUGGGGACAGCUCAAAUGUCUUUAACCUUUGAAGAAGUUGCUGGGGGAAGCUAUUUUUAAUGCUGCCCUGAGGAGCCCUCCAGGGUAUAACUAGAUUGUUCUAGCAGAGUCCUUUCUAGAUCAUCCCAGGAGGUAAGAAGAUUGAACCUCAAUUCUUAAUCCUGUAAUUGGCAAACUUUGCUCCUGCAACUCUUGCACAGCCGAUUCUUCCCAUUUGUUUCCUGGGAAAAAAUCGGGAUACUCGGCCAGGCGUGGUGGCUCACGCCUGUAAUCCCAACACUUUGGGAGGCUGAGACGGGUGAUCACCUGAGGUCAGGAGUUGAAGACCAGCCUGGGCAACAUGAUGAAACGCUGUCUCUACUAAAAAUACAAAAAUUAGCUGGGUGUGGUAGUGGGCACCUGUAAUCCCAGCUACUCGGGAGGCUGAGGUAGGAGAAUUGCUUGAACCUGGGAGGCAGAGGUUGCAGUGAGCCGAGAUUGCAUCAUUGCACUCCAGCCUGGGUGAUGAGCAAAAACUCCAUCUCAAAAAAAAAAAAAAAAAAAAAUCGGGAUACUCACGUCCUUCUGAUCUGGGUCUGGGGUCCUGGGCCAGUGGUUCAUAGUCCCCUCUUUCAGCCUCCAGCCAUCAUUUAGGCCCCGAUACAUCCCAGUCCACACUGUCACUUCCACAGAUGGGAAGACACUGAUACAAUGGAGAUGGAACAGAAAUGGUGCUUGGGCUGGGACUCUCCCAAGUCCACCAACUUCAGGGCCCAGGGCAGGGCAAGGUACUGCUCACAGGGCCACCAGCUCGGGGCCCAUUGCUUCCCUGGUCACUUCUAGCCAUCCUGGCCUGGAACUAGGGUAAUGGGAACCUGGGGAGGGGACUUAGCUGAAGAAAUGCCUACCUCAUGAAAUGGUGGGAAAAAUUUUUCCAGGGGAAAAAUUCAGUCAGGGGAGAAACCUAGGCCUAUUCCUCGGAGGGUUGAUGAGAGCCUGAGCCCCUGAUGUGGGCCACCUCUCCAGCCUCCUCUGCUUUUCUCCCAGUUCUUCCAGAACACUUCUCACUUCCCCGGCUCCUCUCCCCAGACUGUGGUUCUCCACGGAGAGUGGCCCACUUAGCUUCUAGAGGAUGAAGAGAGGGGAGCUCUUUGACUACCUCACUGAGAAGGUCACCUUGAGUGAGAAGGAAACCAGAAAGAUCAUGCGAGCUCUGCUGGAGGUGAUCUGCACCUUGCACAAACUCAACAUCGUGCACCGGGACCUGAAGCCCGAGAACAUUCUCUUGGAUGACAACAUGAACAUCAAGCUCACAGACUUUGGCUUUUCCUGCCAGCUGGAGCCGGGAGAGAGGCUGCGAGUAGAGACAGGGUUUCACCAUGUUGGUCAGGCUGGUCUCGAACUCCUGACCUUACGAUCCGCCCGCCUCGGCCUCCCAAAGUGCUGUGAUUACAGGCGUGAGCCACCAUGCCCAGCAGGGCUAGGCAUUUCUUCAGAGGUCUGCGGGACCCCCAGUUACCUGGCCCCUGAGAUUAUCGAGUGCUCCAUGAAUGAGGACCACCCGGGCUACGGGAAAGAGGUGGACAUGUGGAGCACUGGCGUCAUCAUGUACACGCUGCUGGCCGGCUCCCCGCCCUUCUGGCACCGGAAGCAGAUGCUGAUGCUGAGGAUGAUCAUGAGCGGCAACUACCAGUUUGGCUCGCCCGAGUGGGAUGAUUACUCGGACACCGUGAAGGACCUGGUCUCCCGAUUCCUGGUGGUGCAACCCCAGAACCGCUACACAGCGGAAGAGGCCUUGGCACACCCCUUCUUCCAGCAGUACUUGGUGGAGGAAGUGCGGCACUUCAGCCCCCGGGGGAAGUUCAAGGUGAUCGCUCUGACCGUGCUGGCUUCAGUGCGGAUCUACUACCAGUACCGCCGGGUGAAGCCUGUGACCCGGGAGAUCGUCAUCCGAGACCCCUAUGCCCUCCGGCCUCUGCGCCGGCUCAUCGACGCCUACGCUUUCCGAAUCUAUGGCCACUGGGUGAAGAAGGGGCAGCAGCAGAACCGGGCAGCCCUUUUCGAGAACACACCCAAGGCCGUGCUCCUCUCCCUGGCCGAGGAGGACUACUGAGGGGCUGGCCAGUCAGGGAGGGCUAGGGGGCAGGUGGGGAGGGGAAGCCAUGGAAAUACAAGUCAAAGGGGUGAGAUGCGUGCAGGCCUCUGCAGAAGGAGCACUUGGCCCUGGCCAGGAACCCCUGGAACUGAGGCCACGAUCCCCUCUCAAAGGCUGUGCACAAGGGAAGUGGGUGUUCCCACCACACAGCAAUACCUGCAGGCUGGGGCAGGCCCUGGGUGGGCAGAGAUCACACGUGGCCUGAGAACCAGGAACCCCCUGCUCCUCUACUUCCUAGAUGAGCCACCAUCUCCAUUUCUCUUUAGGGGAGGCCCAGAGUUACUGACACUCAGGCUUUCUUCCCUUAGGGUCACAGGGUGAGGAUCAAAGACACAAAUGUCUGAGAUACACAAUUGCAGGAGAUUUUAUUGGCCCCAUGACAUCCAGUGACAGUGUGGGAGCAGGCUACUCUCCAGGGACAUGUUUUUGGAGGCAUAUGGAGAAGGGGGCCCAGGCGAGGUGGCUCACACCUGUAAUCCCAGCACUUUGGGAGGUCGAGGUGGGAGGAUCGCUUGAGGCCAGGAGUUCGAGACCACCCUGGGCAACAGAGCGAGAUCCCAUCACUACAAAAAUUCAAAAAAUUAGCCAGGCAUGGUGGUGCACACUUGUAGUCCCAGCUACUCAGGAGGCUGAGGUGGGAGAAUUGCUUGGGCCCAGGAAUUCAAGGCUAGAGUGAGCCGUGAUCACCAGUGCACUCUAGCCUGGGCAACAGAGAAA